ACUUGCUCCCAGGCCAGCUCGCUGGCAUUUGGGAGAAUGUGUCAUUGCAUUUACUCAAGGGGGAGGAGGAGGGAAGGUUAGAGAUGAGGAGGCAGAGGUAGGGUGGGAGCAGGGACCUCGCACAGGCAGAGGGGACUCGUGGGGGAUGUUAGCGUGCCUGUGCACGGUGCUCUGGCACCUCCCUGCAGUGCCAGCUCUCAAUCGCACAGGGGACCCAGGGCCUGGCCCCUCCAUCCAGAAAACCUAUGACCUCACCCGCUACCUGGAGCACCAACUCCGCAGCUUGGCUGGGACCUAUCUGAACUACCUGGGCCCCCCUUUCAACGAGCCAGACUUCAACCCUCCCCGCCUGGGGGCAGAGACUCUGCCCAGGGCCACUGUUGACUUGGAGGUGUGGCGAAGCCUCAAUGACAAACUGCGGCUGACCCAGAACUACGAGGCCUACAGCCACCUUCUGUGUUACUUGCGUGGCCUCAACCGUCAGGCUGCCACUGCUGAGCUGCGCCGCAGCCUGGCCCACUUCUGCACCAGCCUCCAGGGCCUGCUGGGCAGCAUUGCGGGCGUCAUGGCAGCUCUGGGCUACCCACUGCCCCAGCCGCUGCCUGGGACUGAACCCACUUGGACUCCUGGCCCUGCCCACAGUGACUUCCUCCAGAAGAUGGACGACUUCUGGCUGCUGAAGGAGCUGCAGACCUGGCUGUGGCGCUCGGCCAAGGACUUCAACCGGCUCAAGAAGAAGAUGCAGCCUCCAGCAGCUGCAGUCACCCUGCACCUGGGGGCUCAUGGCUUCUGACUUCUGACCUUCUCCUCUUCGCUCCCCCUUCAAACCCUGCUCCCACUUUGUGAGAGCCAGCCCUGUAUGCCAACACCUGUUGAGCCAGGAGACAGAAGCUGUGAGCCUCUGGCCCUUUCCUGGACCGGCUGGGCGUGUGAUGCGAUCAGCCCUGUCUCCUCCCCACCUCCCAAAGGUCUACCGAGCUGGGGAGGAGGUACAGUAGGCCCUGUCCUGUCCUGUUUCUACAGGAAGUCAUGCUCGAGGGAGUGUGAAGUGGUUCAGGUUGGUGCAGAGGCGCUCAUGGCCUCCUGCUUCUUGCCUACCACUUGGCCAGUGCCCACCCAGCCCCUCAGGUGGCACAUCUGGAGGGCAGGGGUUGAGGGGCCACCACCACACAUGCCUUUCUGGGGUGAAGCCCUUUGGCUGCCCCACUCUCCUUGGAUGGGUGUUGCUCCCUUAUCCCCAAAUCACUCUAUACAUCCAAUUCAGGAAACAAACAUGGUGGCAAUUCUACACAAAAAGAGAUGAGAUUAACAGUGCAGGGUUGGGGUCUGCAUUGGAGGUGCCCUAUAAACCAGAAGAGAAAAUACUGAAAGCACAGGGGCAGGGACAGACCAGACCAGACCCAGGAGUCUCCAAAGCACAGAGUGGCAAACAAAACCCGAGCUGAGCAUCAGGACCUUGCCUCGAAUUGUCUUCCAGUAUUACGGUGCCUCUUCUCUGCCCCCUUUCCCAGGGUAUCUGUGGGUUGCCAGGCUGGGGAGGGCAACCAUAGCCACACCACAGGAUUUCCUGAAAGUUUACAAUGCAGUAGCAUUUUGGGGUGUAGGGUGGCAGCUCCCCAAGGCCCUGCCCCCCAGCCCCACCCACUCAUGACUCUAAGUGUGUUGUAUUAAUAUUUAUUUAUUUGGAGAUGUUAUUUAUUAGAUGAUAUUUAUUGCAGAAUUUCUAUUCUUGUAUUAACAAAUAAAAUGCUUGCCCCAGAA